AACACAGCUGAGGUCACCUCCCUGAGAACUAAGAGGAUGAACUAAAUGACCAGAUUAGAUUUUCAAGGAAAAUCUAAAAUAACACUGAGUUCCUUCCUCCUGGCCCUUCACUCACAGUCCACAGUGACCCACACGUUCUCUCCCUUGAGAGACAAAAUGAGGCAGAUGGAAUUCAUGAAGACUGUCAAGAUGCUGGAUGAGUUUGGUGUAGAAGGCUUUUGUCCUACAGGGAGACUGCAUGUGUGUUUGGUGCCCGUUUAUAGCAAUAACAACAAGAGCUACCCAUCUGAUCUGAGGUCGGGCAGCAUGCUGAGUGCUUAAUGCACAGUACCGCAUUUAACCCUCCCCUGCCAAAACCCUGUGAGGUGGGCAAUUGUCCUCAUUUUGCUAAUGAGAACACUGAAGCUCAGAAAGUCACUUGCUUUAGAGAAUUAUAACAAUAAUAAUGAAAGCAAUAAGGCUGUUUUUUACUGCAGGCUUCUUCUGAGCCAAUACUGAGGUGUGGAUAUUGCAUUCAUGAUUUGAUUUAAUUCUCACAAGUCCUGUUGAGGGCAUGACAUAUUUUUUACUCCUAAUAGGGCAGCACCUUAUUAAUCUUUCAGCCAAAUUUGCUAAUGUCAAAAUAAUAUAUAUGCCUUAAUUUAUUGAACAUAUUAGAAUUCUUAAAACCCUUCAUCCUUCUCUAUUCUCUACUGAUAUUCUUAUAAUUCUUUAUUUUGAUAUAAUUUCCAAUUUAUGGAAAAGUCCUGGGAAUAGUACAAGGGACUUCCAUAUGCCCUUUGCCCUGAUUUACCAACUGUUUACAGUUUUACCCCAUUUAUUUUAUCAUUAUCUCUCCCCCAUCUCUUACGUGUAUCUUAAUACUUUUUCCAAAACCUUUGAUGGUAAAUUUGAGACAUACAUCAUGCCUAUUUGCCCCUAAGUACUUCAGUGAGUAUUUUCUAAGAACAAGAGUAUUCUCUUCUAUAACUGCAAUACCUUUAUCAAAGUUAGAAAACAAACAUUGAUUGACAUUAGUGUUUAAUUCGUAGUCUAUAUCCAAAUUUUGUCAAUUGUCCCAAAGUCCUUUACAGCUGUUUUCCCUCCUCUGGUCCAUAAUCUAAUCCAGGAUCAUUUACUAUACAUUUGGCCACCAAGUCUGUCUCCUUCAUAAACAAACAAUUCCUAAGGUUUUGUCUUUUUGAUUUUUGCAUUUUUGAAGAGUUUUGGACAGGGAUUUAAUUUGCUUUAUCUGAUGUUUCUUCAUGGUGUGAUUCAAGUUAUAUGUUUUUGGCAGGAAUAACCCAAAAGUGAAGUUAUAUCUUUCUUGGUUCAUCAUAUUAUGAAGCAAAUAAUGUUGGCUUGUUCCAAUACUGAUAAUAACUUUAAUGACUUCAUUAAGGUGGUAUCUGCCAGGUUUUUCUAAAGUUAGUAUUUUUCCUUUUGUAAUUAACAAAUAAGUUAUGGGAAGAUAAUUUCAGGAUAUGUAGUAUUCUGUCUUUAAAUUUUACUCACUAAUUUUAACAUUCACUGAUAAUUUCAAUCUUUCUGAAUUUGUUAGUGGGUAUUGUACUGUAAAUCAAUGUUUUGUAUUUACUAAUUGGCAUUCUGUAAAUAAGAGCUUUUCCUUCCAAUUAUUUAUUUGUUCAUUUAUUUAUUGGUCUCUAUAUGGACUUGAACAUUCUUAAUUUAUUCAAUGGGAUAUAAUUAUUUACUAUAAUUAUUUUGAUGCUCAAUAUUUCUGUAUUUGAACAGUGGGAGCUCCUUCAAGCUGGCUUGUGGGUCCUUUUGACAUGAAGGUCUCUUAAUCACUAAACCAUUAUAUAUAUGUGGUAUACAUAUACCUUAAUAAUCAUACUAUACCAUCUACUGGGGCACUUUCAAUAUUUCUGAAGAGCCCAGACAAGUCUGAUAAUAAUUACACAAAACAAAGAACAGAAGUUAAACUUUAUAGAUUCUUUUUCUGCCGGGCAACAUGCCAUCCAUUUCUUGUGCUCUAUUUUAUUAAAGCAUAACAAAAAUCUUAUUUUACUGAUGAGGAAAUCAAGGCACACACCAAAGGUCAAGUAAUUGGCCAAGAUAACUAAGCUAGCAAGCAGCUGAAUCAAGAUCUGAACACAGGUUCCAGGCCUGUGGUGUUACUGCAGCAUGGCCUAGUUGGAGGUGCUAGCAACUGGAUUUCCAACCUGCCCAACAAUAGCCUGGGCUUCAUUCUGGCAGAUGCUGGUUUUGACGUGUGGAUGGGGAACAGCAGGGGAAACGCCUGGUCUCGAAAACACAAGACACUCUCCAUAGACCAAGAUGAGUUCUGGGCUUUCAGUUAUGAUGAGAUGGCUAGGUUUGACCUUCCUGCAGUGAUAAACUUUAUUUUGCAGAAAACGGGCCAGGAAAAGAUCUAUUAUGUCGGCUAUUCACAGGGCACCACCAUGGGCUUUAUUGCAUUUUCCACCAUGCCAGAGCUGGCUCAGAAAAUCAAAAUGUAUUUUGCUUUAGCACCCAUAGCCACUGUUAAGCAUGCAAAAAGCCCCGGGACCAAAUUUUUGUUGCUGCCAGAUAUGAUGAUCAAGGGAUUGUUUGGCAAAAAAGAAUUUCUGUAUCAGACCAGAUUUCUCAGACAACUUGUUAUUUACCUUUGUGGCCAGGUGAUUCUUGAUCAGAUUUGUAGUAAUAUCAUGUUACUUCUGGGUGGAUUCAACACCAACAAUAUGAACAUGAAUACUCAUGGUUUGUUACAGAGCCGAGCAAGUGUAUAUGCUGCCCACACUCUUGCUGGAACAUCUGUGCAAAAUAUUCUACACUGGAGCCAGGCAGUGAAUUCUGGUGAACUCCGGGCAUUUGACUGGGGGAGUGAGACCAAAAAUCUGGAAAAAUGCAAUCAGCCAACUCCUGUAAGGUACAGAGUCAGAGAUAUGACGGUCCCUACAGCAAUGUGGACAGGAGGUCAGGACUGGCUUUCAAAUCCAGAAGACGUGAAAAUGCUGCUCUCUGAGGUGACCAACCUCAUCUACCAUAAGAAUAUUCCUGAAUGGGCUCACGUGGAUUUCAUCUGGGGUUUGGAUGCUCCUCACCGUAUGUACAAUGAAAUCAUCCAUCUGAUGCAGCAGGAGGAGACCAACCUUUCCCAGGGACGGUGUGAGGCCGUAUUGUGAAGCAUCUGACACUGACGAUCUUAGGACAACCUCCUGAGGGAUGGG